GGCCUCCCAAAGUGCUGGGAUUACGGGCGUCAGACACCACGCCCAACCAGAGUCCACUUGUUAUGCUAAAGGAGAGCUCUUCUGCAGGAUUUUUGGCAUUUUUCUUAAAGUUUUCAUGUAUAGCUAAGACAAUUUUUUAAUUGUGAAAAGGUUUGUCCCUAGUGGCUUCAAAAUGUCAACCUGUUGGAAGAACAAUCCCAGUUGAACCAAUGUGACUUUCUUCUCAUACUCUACUUAACUCACAGAAACAGAUGUGGUGGCAGAACAAGCUGAAGCUGUCAGUUUUUUAAUCUUUUCAGGUUUCUGAGAGUGGGACACACAUGUGUGCUAUGAUUCCAAAGAUGGAACACCUUUCAUUUAAUGUGUUAAGUUCGUCAGUAUACAGAUGUAGUUGGUUUACACUGAUAACAGAUGCAGAAGUGAAACUGAAAUGCACAGUAAGGACAAUCUGAAAACAACUACAACAACAAAACAACAACAACAACAACAACAACAAAACCCUGUGUUUGGGGUUUGCAGGAGCCUGGGUCUACUCAGCUUAGUUACCAACUGGAUGUGAAAGUUCCCACCAGACCCCUUCAGGAUCCAUAUCCUCACUGUGUGGUGAAGAGUUGGACUUGACAAAACCAUUUCUCAUUUCCCAUCUUGCUCUGAUUUUUUCCAGUUUUCUCUAGUACAUAUUCUUUUAUGAUUGCUUUUAUUUUAAGCAUGUGGAGUUUAAUAGUGAGCCAAUGCCAUCAGAUAAAUUCUGCCUCCUUUCCUAGUUUAGUUUCUCUUUGUGAGUGGAAUCCCCCUUAUGUUUCUGAACUAUUUAAGAGGCUUGCUUUGUGAUGGAAGAGGAAAUGCCAAAAGUGACUCCAAUAAUGUCACUUUAAGUCAUUUUCUGUUUCUUUACAUGAUUUCUAGUUUUACAGGGGCUUUAAAAAAGAAUAGGAAAUAGGAAUAGGAAAUCACUUUAAGUCAUCUUCUUUCUUUGCAUGAUUUCUAGUUUUACAGGGCUUUUUAAAAAGGAAUAAGAAAUAUGAAAAAACUGGGGAAAGGUUGGUGAUUUGACAAUAUUUUACUUGUACUUUUUUUUUUUUUUUUUUUUUUUGAGAUGGAGUUUUGCUCUUGUUGCCCAGGCUGGAGUGCAAUGGCGUGAUCUAGGCUCACUGCAACCUCAGCCUCCUGGGUUCAAGCGAGUCUCCUGCCUCAGACUCCCUAGUAGCUGGGAUUACAGGCGCCCGCCACCACGCCCAGCUAAUUUUUUGCAUUUUUAGUAGAGAUGGGAUUUCACUGUUGAAACUAUGGCCAGGCUGGUCUGGAACUCCAGAUCUCAGGCCAUCCACCCGCCUCAGCCUCCCAAAGUGUUGGGAUUACAGGCGUGAGCUACCGCGCCCAGCAGACUUGUACUUUUUAAGUGUUUCAUAUCCUAUUUGAGCGGCUAUCUUUGUUUACCUAGGUAAUGUAGUCAUAUGUACUGUGUUCAGAAAUCAAGAGAGUAAAAGGAAGCAAUAGAAAGGAAAGGAUAGUUUUCAGAGCUGAGAUAUAUUUUUCAAAAAAAUCAUGGCCCAGCUGUUUCUACUGGGGACACCUAGAGUAGGGCAAUGGGAGAUGAUAAUGUGGUUAGCCCAAGGUUGUUUAGGUGGUUUUAGUUAGUUUGUUUUGAAACCUGAAGCCUCAGUGGGCUUGAGCAACAAGGAAUAGAGAUAGAGAAUUCUCAUCAUUUUGUGAAGCUUUGUGAGCUUUUUCAUUCUUUUACAUCUCCGUUUUCCACAGUAGCCUCAGGAUUUUCUUUAUAUGGAUGCAUGCCGGGGGCUUCCCGAUGAUCACUUGAGGAUGGCUCUGGUGAGACAGAGAACUUGGUGGAAAUCCCCCUGAGCUGCCUUCCUGGAAUAAACCUGGGUUGAGAAAUCUUGGGGCUCUGGGCACACAGAAAAUGCCUGGUGGACAAAUCAUGGGACUGCUACCACCAUCUUAUCAAACGUGAUUAAUGGGAACUGGAAUGUAAUGGAGAGACAGUGUCACAUCCCUGCAGGGUGUCUCUGUGUUUUUUUCCUUCCCAAACACUGUCUUUCUCUCUUUCUUUUAAUGGAUUUUCAAACAAUACUCUGGUAGCACCUUUUGUGCUACAGGCAUCUGCCACUUGCAGCAGAUUUAAAGGAUUUAGACCUGGAGGGUAAAGAGUAAUUUCUCCGAAAGGAUCUUGACGUGUUACUGUUAUAAUAAGCUAAGCAGUUUGUCUUUUUUUUAAAUUAAAAAUAUGUUUGUUUGGCUUACAUAAACGAUAGUGUCUUCUGUUAAGAAAGAAAAAAAGGACAGGAGAAGCACAUUAUUCUGGAUUUUUCCUUACCUUUGAUCAAGGCUUUACAUAUAACUUCCUGACUCCAGGAAACACCAGGGAUAGAAGAACAAGGUCAGCAACACUUUGAGCAAGCACUAUGCUAAAUCUAGAAUUUGGGGCAUCCUAUAGGACAGUGGAACCAGUUUAGUUAAUGAGUCAGUGGCCUGUGAAAAGAAGGAAAAAAGGAAGAGAUAACUAUUCUAUGUUAAAAGGGAUUAAGGGAUCUCAGAGACAUAAGGAAAUAUAAUGAGUAGACAUUGUUAGGAUUCUUAUUUGUGAACAAGUGGAAAACAGAUUUAAAAAUAAUUGGGGAAAUGUGAAUGUGAACUAGCUUUUGAUAGUAUUAAGGAAUUACUAUUAAUUUUGUUAUAAAUGAUAAUAACCUUAUGGUUAUAUAAGCAUCUCUGCUUCCAUUCCCACAUGAAUACAAAUGAAGCAAGUCCCUUAAUCUCACUUAGGAUUAGUAUUUGCAGCUACAAAGAAGAUGCUUAUUUUGGAAGGUUUUGUAGGGUUGACGUGGAGGUAGAAUGAGACAAUGCUAGCGUAGAAUCCUGUGAGUGAUUUUUAUGUUUCGUUGUUGUUGUUGUUGUUUUUGGCUAUCAUUAUCACUAUAUGAGGUUCAUGUAUCAUAUUAAUUCUAACUCUAGCUAUCCUUUAAAACUUUCAUGUGUUUCCAUUUCUUUUCCUAUUGGUGAUCAUACUGGUGUCCCACCUUUCAACGUUCGCAGGUAUUCCAGAUGGCCUGCUCCAUGAGAUAGAGGUGUCUUGGUUCAUCUUGGCCUUGCUCACCACUUACUCUUACCACAAGGUCCUGUGUCAGGCCCAGCAAUUGCCCUUGAAUAGAUGCUGACUUAUUUGUUGAAUGAAUGAACUCUCCCUGUUAAACUUAAAGCAGAAAAAAGGAACUUUAUUGCAGCUUCUUAUUGGCAGUAAAUGCUAACAGAUUUAUAUUGAUAAGCUGCUGGGAGAGGACUUAAAAGGGGCCUACAUCUCACAUUAGUGUUUUUAGUUGCUUGCCUAUUGCUCAUGAUCAAUCCCCUCUCAUUCCUCUUCCUCAGAAAGUAGGCACGUGGUCAUUUCUUUUUUUCAUCAAGAUUGCAAAGUCUUUAUACAGUGAGGAAGAAAUUGUAUUAGAAUCCUUACGUUUUGCACAUAGUAGGCAGUUGCUAAAUGUCAAAAGAAGACUUUAUUUCUGUACCCAAAAUAUUUUUAGAUAUUUUGAUGGGAACUGGGAGAGCUGGGAGAAUAUUCAGUGUAAGAAAUGAUUUUUUUCUGUGAGUCAAGAAAAUAUCGUAGAAAUACUGUGAUAGCCUUUAAUUUAUAGCUGUCAAAUACUGACUUGGUUAAAAUUAUUACAAUGCUUCAGAGGCAAUUAUUUACAUAUGUUUUCUCUCUUCAUCUUUAAUAUAGUAACGUGGAAGCGGGAAGCUGGGAGAAAGUCAUUUUUUAAAUGUGGAUUGAGAGUUCAUAUGUGGAAAGGGCUGCAAUUCAUUGAAAUAACCAGGAGAAAUUGGAUGCUGAUAUUUCAGAGCUGCAGUCUGUUUGGAACCUCACAGUACCGCAGUCUAACAAAGAAGUGCCAGCUUUGUUUUAGAUUUAAAAGAGUAUCAUCUAAAGGAUCUGACAUUACAGACAAAAGAGAGAUCUGUCUAUGGCAGUGCAGAAAUUUUCCCAGUCAUUGCAAGAUUUCCAGUUUGAAUGUAUUGGUGAUGCUGAAACAGAUGAUGAAAUUAGUAUUGCUCAGUCACUAAAAGAAUUUGCAAGACUACUCAUUGCAGUAGAAGAAGAAAGGCGAAGACUGAUCCAAAACGCUAACGAUGUAUUAAUUGCACCACUUGAGAAAUUUCGAAAAGAACAGAUAGGUGCAGCAAAAGAUGGAAAGAAGAAGUUUGACAAAGAGAGUGAAAAAUAUUACUCUAUCCUUGAAAAGCAUUUAAAUUUGUCCGCAAAGAAAAAGGAGUCUCAUUUACAAGAGGCAGAUACACAAAUUGACCGAGAACAUCAGAACUUCUAUGAAGCAUCAUUAGAAUAUGUCUUUAAAAUUCAAGAGGUCCAAGAAAAAAAGAAGUUUGAAUUUGUUGAACCGCUUUUGUCAUUUCUUCAGGGCUUAUUUACUUUUUACCAUGAGGGAUAUGAACUUGCCCAGGAAUUUGCACCGUAUAAGCAACAGCUGCAGUUCAACUUGCAGAAUACAAGGAAUAAUUUUGAAAGUACUCGACAAGAGGUAGAGCGGUUGAUGCAAAGGAUGAAAUCUGCUAACCAGGACUACAGACCACCCAGCCAGUGGACGAUGGAAGGCUAUCUGUAUGUCCAGGAGAAACGACCGCUUGGUUUUACAUGGAUUAAACAUUAUUGUACAUAUGAUAAGGGAAGUAAAACAUUUACAAUGAGUGUUUCAGAAAUGAAAUCCAGUGGGAAAAUGAAUGGCCUUGUUACUAGCUCACCGGAAAUGUUUAAAUUAAAAUCUUGUAUCCGACGAAAGACAGAUUCAAUUGACAAACGAUUCUGCUUUGACAUAGAAGUAGUUGAAAGGCAUGGGAUCAUCACGUUACAGGCCUUCUCAGAAGCUAAUAGGAAACUCUGGCUUGAAGCCAUGGAUGGGAAGGAACCGAUUUAUACUCUGCCUGCCAUUAUAAGCAAGAAAGAAGAAAUGUAUUUGAAUGAAGCAGGGUUCAACUUUGUGAGAAAAUGCAUUCAAGCUGUGGAAACAAGAGGUAUCACCAUUUUAGGACUCUACCGAAUAGGAGGAGUGAACUCCAAAGUUCAAAAACUCAUGAAUACCACAUUUUCUCCUAAAUCCCCUCCUGAUAUUGAUAUUGAUAUUGAACUGUGGGACAAUAAGACGAUAACAAGUGGGCUGAAAAACUACCUCAGGUGCCUUGCAGAACCACUGAUGACUUACAAGUUGCACAAAGAUUUUAUCAUUGCUGUUAAAUCUGAUGAUCAAAACUACAGGGUGGAGGCUGUACAUGCAUUGGUGCACAAAUUGCCGGAGAAAAACAGAGAGAUGCUGGACAUCUUAAUAAAGCAUCUGGUCAAAGUAUCACUACACAGCCAACAAAAUCUCAUGACUGUCUCAAAUCUUGGUGUCAUAUUUGGCCCAACUCUAAUGAGAGCACAGGAAGAAACUGUGGCUGCUAUGAUGAAUAUUAAAUUUCAGAAUAUUGUGGUAGAAAUUCUGAUAGAGCACUAUGAAAAGAUUUUUCAUACUGCUCCAGACCCAAGCAUUCCUCUUCCUCAGCCUCAGUCUCGAUCUGGAUCCCGAAGGACACGAGCAAUCUGCCUCUCUACAGGGUCUAGGAAGCCCAGAGGGAGGUAUACUCCAUGCCUGGCCGAACCUGAUAGUGACUCCUAUAGCAGCAGCCCAGACAGCACACCUAUGGGGAGCAUUGAGUCACUCUCUUCUCAUUCCUCUGAACAAAAUAGCACUACAAAGUCAGCUUCCUGCCAGCCCAGGGAGAAAUCUGGAGGGAUUCCUUGGAUUGCAACCCCAUCAUCUUCCAAUGGACAGAAAAGCCUUGGUCUGUGGACAACUAGUCCUGAAUCAAGUUCCAGAGAAGAUGCAACCAAGACAGAUGCAGAAUCAGACUGCCAGAGUGUUGCUUCAGUCACUAGCCCAGGAGACGUUUCCCCACCCAUAGACCUAGUCAAGAAAGAGCCUUAUGGGCUUUCAGGACUGAAAAGAGCUUCUGCUUCUUCUCUCAGAUCCAUCUCUGCAGCUGAAGGAAACAAGAGCUACAGUGGAUCUAUUCAAAGCUUAACUUCUGUAGGUUCCAAGGAGACACCCAAAGCUUCACCAAACCCAGACCUGCCUCCGAAAAUGUGCAGGAGAUUAAGACUAGACACUGCCUCAAGCAAUGGCUAUCAGCGGCCUGGCUCAGUAGUGGCAGCAAAAGCUCAACUGUUUGAAAAUGUUGGUUCACCUAAACCAGUUUCUUCUGGGCGCCAAGCCAAAGCCAUGUACUCCUGUAAAGCAGAGCACAGUCAUGAGCUUUCCUUCCCACAAGGAGCAAUAUUUUCUAAUGUGUACCCAUCAGUGGAACCAGGAUGGUUAAAGGCAACUUAUGAAGGCAAAACAGGACUAGUUCCAGAAAAUUAUGUUGUCUUCCUCUAAUACUAUUUAGUGGAUGGCAGUAUCUUCAUGGUAUCCAUGGUAACGAAUAAAUGCUAUGAUUUUAUCUGACACAGAUACACGGGGAUCAGCCCACUAAGUGAAAACAGUCAAUUUCUAUCAAGUUCUUCACCAGCAGACUAUGUAGCUCCUUAUUAAUGGAAAAAAAGAUUUAAAUUGUUGGCCAUUCUUUUUUGGUUGGUUUCUUAUUUUAAAAUAUCUUACUUGUGAAAAAUGUGUUUUUGGAUAAUAUGUAACUCUCCACAAUGUCGCUUCCGUAGCAAUUGUAGAGUUUCAAAUACUGUGUUAAAUACUGUAUCCCAGAAAUUUGGAAACCAGAAAUCUGCUAUAUGGAUUUUGAGAUCUGUCCUUUACUGCCUGGCAUUCUCUGAGGAUCUCUGAAAUUGUUACUUAAAAAUGUAAUUUAAAUUGUUCAUUUAUUGUUUUUUUUUUCUUAGAAAUAUACUGCUUUUAUAUAUGAUUGUUUUGCUGGUCCUAAACAUUUCAAGGAUGUAAGUCUUUGUUUUAAUAUAACUUUAUUUGUUUUCCAAGUAGAUGAUAAUAUUCAAAAGCAAUAAUGUAUAUGAUAUCUAUAAAGGAAGCAAAAUUAAGUCAUACACUGAUUCCACUGUAAACAAUCUGUCCAGAAUUCCAGACACCUUCAGCAAACUUUUUCUGUAAAGGCCUGAUAGCAAAUAUUUUUGUGGUGGGUUGAAUUUGGCUUAUGGGUUAUAGUUUGCUGACACCUAGUUUAGAGGGUGUGUAAAACUAUCUUCAUAACUUUGAGAUUUUUAUAAAAUUUUACAUGAAAAUAUACUGAUAAAUUAUAUGCACAUAUUUUCUACCAGUAGCAUUAUAGUGGCAUCAUAGAAGAAUAUUUACCAAUGAUGGGGAAACUGUAAAACUACAGUAUCAAGGCAUACAACUUAAAUUCCACUUGGAAGAUUGUAAAGUGUCAAAGUAUUUUAAUGAUAAUUUAAUUUGGGCUUUUGAAAUGUUCUUCUACAAAUGAAAAAGAUGUUUAAAAACGUUACAAGGGAAGCUAUGCCUUCUGAAGUCUAUCCUUAGUUGAAACAGAAAAUAAACACAAAGGUACAAGAUCCUUAAAUUAUUUUGAACCACAGAGGUUGAAAUUGUUUUGUGAUCUUCAGCAGAAAUAAAAUCUGUACAUGAUUUUCUUUUAUGCCUUUUAGUUUACAGUCUUUAUUAGCAAUUUCAGUGAAUUUGUAGAGCAUAGUAAUAGGUAUUUACUGUCCACUUAUAUAUAUCAGCAUCUGGUCAUGCACGAACCAUUAAUUCUAUAUUUCUAUUUCAAUAAUUCUAAUAUAUUAUUUCUAUAAAUGUAAUAUCUGUAUGUGGCAAAGAGCCUUUCUUCUCAAGAUCCUGAAAAGCUGGUUACCUGCCCUUUGAGUGCCACAGUCCUGAACUGCUUGUUCUUGACAUCUUGCAUAUUACUUCAGAGUUCCCCACUGUGCAGACUCUCAGGUAUUAACUGUAAAAAACUCUUUACAUGCCAUUAUUAUCUGUAAUCUCUAUCUCUUCUACUUUAAAUUAAUGUUUCUAGAAUUAAUAGGUUAAAUACACAUACACACACACAACUAUGCCUCAGAAAAGUUAGGCUUUUACAAAUAAAAAGAAUAAGAUUAGAAUUAACAAGUAGAGAGAAUAACGGUAGGCAGAGUCAGAAUCAGGAAUAAAUAUCAGUGAAUCAAAAGAAUGAAAAAUAUUAUGUAAUAAAAAUUAGCAAUGUAAUGUAAACGUUUGAUAAAAGAGUAUCUUUUUCUUUUAUCUCUUACUGUUGACCUCUGUGCACUGUAAUAAGGUGUGUUGCUGGAUCUUCUUGGUCGAGGUCCUUGGUGACCUUAGUAGUAAUAACAGCAUUGCUGACACCCUAAUUGCCCUCUGCUGGAACAGAAGGUAGUUUUCCAGUGUACCAGUCCCUUAGUCUAUACAGCACCCUUGGUUUAAGCACACUUGCCAUCAUCUGGUAUCCUGCUAGACUAGAAUCUCUUAAAAGCAAAUUGGUUUUCUUUCAAAGACCAACUUGACUCCAAAGAGAGAUUCAGAAUCCUACUUCUCCUGCUGCUGCAUAAAGAAUCUCAACCUUCAUUUUAUUUGAACACGGACCAAAGUGUUCCUGCUUCUGAGUUGUCUGUAAGCUAAUUCUGCAGAUGUUCCAUUCAGAUUUAAAGCUUUUUUACUGCAUAGGAUGUGGAUAGGAAGCCUAACUAUUGUAUCUGAUGGCAAGGCAUAUGUUGCAGCCACAGUACUGGCUAUGGUCCCUUUGCUGAAACAAGCUACAGAAGCACUGAUUCAAGUUGUGCUUGUGCUUGAACUUUUAAUCUUCUAGAUUUGUGAGGAUGGCUCUUUUUCCUUCAUAAUGGAUUACAAUGUAAGCAAGUCAUGGCCAUAUACUGGAGACGGGCUAAAGCUGCUUUUCCCUUAAAGUAAGUUUCCUACAGAUAAGGUAUUUAUGAGCACUGAGAAAGUCAGGACAUGUACUCUAAAUCACACAGAAUGUUAAUUCCACAGGAAGGCAAUGCCAGACAUUGAAAGAGGAUCACAUUCAACUUUUAAUAGUAGUUCAAUAACAAAACCUUAGCUUUUCAGGAACAAUGUGAAGAUACAUUAGAAUUGCCACAUCCAUAUCUUCAAAACACGCAACCUCUGCACCCUAAUAACUGCUUACGGUAUAAUCAGUAUGAUGAUGAGAUUGAGGGGGUCUAAAUUUAAGUUCCUUAUCUCCUGAGUUAUGUGAAAAUAUCCCUCAGUACAAAACAUUUGUGUGUUUCACAGAUGACUCUCUUGUUUUGCCGUAAUGCUACCAAGUUUAUGGAAACUAGUCAACUGAAGGAUUUUUCUGUUGUGUUAUGUGUAAAUGUCUGAACAGUAAAAUCAUCUGUGUAUUCCUGUAACAUUCACGAAGUAUGAGGAAGUGGGUUUCUCCUUGUUUGAUGUGAGUGGUUUUGCUUGUUGCAUGGGUUCCCUGUGCUUUGUAACUUGCAUGAACACAACCAGGUUUCUCAACAAUGAUUUGUCUGCUGACUCUUUUCAGAGAUAGUGAAGGAAAAAAAAUGUAUUAAAACCCCAAAUUAUCUAGGUUUCCAAGUAGGAAAAAUAAAGAUACAUAUGACUUUUAUUAUUAUUCGAUGAUAAUUAGCUUUAUAUAAUGUGGCAUCCUUCAUAAAAAUUCACUAUGUUGUGAGGCAAACAGAUUUCUCACUAUCAUCCAGUGUACCCUGCUCACCUUCUCACUCCUAGCACCGUUCUUCUGGUCUGUGUUGAAAAGGGUAUCAUUCAUGUGGUUUCAGUUUAGAAGAGUCCCUCAGAGCUUUGCCUCAAGCAAUUUCAAAUUGUAGUGAUACCUUAAAUCAUGUAUUCAGGAUGCCUUCUUUAGCAUUUAGAACCCCAACUAGACUUAUACUUUGACUAAAGUCAGAGGCAGACCAAUUUAGGGAACAGAUUUUGUUCUUUGCUUUUAUGAUACAUUUGUAACUCACAGCUGUUAGCAUGACCUCACAUCACUGCGUAGGACCCGGAAAUCACAUCUCCUGGUCAGGUCACGAAAAAGAACACAGGCUUGACUAUUGUCCAGAAGUUACUUUCCCCUUGACUAAAGGUUUCCCCUUAGGGUACACAUUGCUAUUUAACUUUGCCUCCUACCCUUUUUUGUUACCUUCCAAAAUCAAGACACUUUUAAGAAACAAAGAUAGUUUUCUGAACAUUCUGUGUCCUGCCUGUCUCCUGUUGAUUCGCAGAUGUAAUAUCGAGUAUUCAUCAACUGGUCUCAAUUUCCUGAACACAUUCACUGUAUCCCUCAUUGUCACCGUUAUCCCCCUGCUUCAAAAUGUGCCAGUUCCACUUGGUAAUAACGUUGGGAAAAUGCAGGUUUAUGAAUGAUGUGGACUUUUAGAGGAUCAAAUCAAUAAAUUGGAUUUUUUAUUUUUUGAGGGCAGCUGCCCUCACUGUUUUAAAUAAAGAAUCUUACAUAAGAAUGUUGACAACAUUCACAGUAAGCCAUUGGCAGAAAAUUGAUCUGCAUGUCCUAGACCAAUGAUUACAAGGUGUCUGUGGUUUAGGGGGCCCAGCCCAUCAUUCCUUUUCCCCUUGGCACUCAUGAGAGAGAUGCCAAGUUCAGUGUGGAUUUUUCUUGGUGCUCUAUGGAGAAAUGGAGUCUGUGUGCUUACUGAAGAGUCCCAAAAACCAGAGACCAUUUUCAUUUACUGCCAUCAUAAAUAUUCUCCACCAUUCAAGAUGCCUGUGUACACGGCUAUUUGGGAAACUUAAGUGUUGGAGGAGGCAGGGGCUGAAGGUGUCAAAACCUCCUCAGUAGGAUAACCCCUUUCUCCCCUUUGGACCAUCUGCCAUCUUUCAUGAGUGUUUCCCAUGGUGUUUUUGCAUCCAGAGUUGACAACAACUCAAUUUUGCCUUGAAUUUACUCAGUCUUAUAAAUUAAAAAUGUGCAUUUUAUAUAAAGAUGCAUUUUAUAUAAAAAUGCACACCUUUAAUCUCUAUAUGGCAGCAUAUACAUAUAUAUAUAUAAAAUGCACACUUUUAAUCUCUAUAUGGCAGCAUUUUUGAGGCUUUAUAUCUGCCCGUGUACCCUCAACUGCCUCCUUUUUGCAGAGAACGAUCCCCACAGGAACUGGUCUAAGAACACUGUCUGCACAUGAUUGAUGCUUAAAAUCCAAUAUACCACCACAUAUCAAAGGUUGGGAUUUUCAGAGUCCUUCUUGAUUUCUGAGCUGAAACCUUAACAAAUAGGGAAUUUGGCAGGGAAGACACCUGGGUUUUUAAUUCAGAACCCUAUUUAUAUACUGUUAAAAUUUGAGGUACUGUAGUUUAUAUAAAAGUCGGAUGUUAAGAUAUUAUAUUUCAGUACUAGGAGCUUCUUUGCAGUCAUUAACAUGACAAAUUAAGUAAUAAAUAUAAAAGUGAUUGUCCAUAAAUUAUCAUUGAAUUUUUUGUUUAUUUUGUAGUGUUCUGUAUUUAUCUGCACUUUGUGUAUAUAUACACACAUACAUAUGCCAACAUGUAAAUAACCUCAUGUUUAUUCCUAAUCUAAAUUGCCACAAUAUUUUUAAUGUAUGGUUACACUGUGUUUUAAAUUACUUUAAAAAUAAACUUUGUAAGCAGAUUUUAA